UUUUAUUUUUUAUUUUUGAGACAAGUUCUCUGUCUCCCAGGCUGAAGUGCAGUGGUGCGAUCUUGGCUCACUGCAACCUCCGCCUCCUGGGUUCAAGUGAUUCUGGUGUCUUAGCCUCCCAAGUAGCUGGGACUACAGGCAUGUGCCACCACUCCCAACUAAUUUUCUGUAUUUUUAGUAGAGACGAGGUUUUACCAUGUUGGCCAGGCUGGUCUCAAACCCCUGACCUCAAGUGAUCCGCCUGCCUCAGCCUCCCAAAGUGCUGGAAUUACAGGCAUGAGCCACUGCACCUGGCCCAUUGUUAGUUUUUAAAAAUACAGGAUUUAGGCUGGGCGUGGUGGCUCAUGCCUGUGAUCCCAGCACUUCGGGAAGCCGCGGCGGGCGGAUCACUUGAGGUCAGGGGUUUGAGACCAGCCUGACCAACAUGGUGAAACCCCGUCUCUACCAAAAAAAUACAAAAAUUAGCCAGGCGUAGUGGCACAUGCCUAUGAUCCCAGCUACUGUGGAGGCUGAGGCAGGAGAAUCUCUUGAAGCCGGGAGGUGGAGGUUGCAGUGAGCUGAGAUCAUGCCACUGCACUCCAGCCUGGGGGACAGAGCGAGACUCCGUCUCAAAAAUAAAUAAAUAACUAAAAACAAACAAAAGCUAACCAUGGAAAAUGAUAUUGAUGGAUCCAAGUGAUACAGUUUGUUUCAACAUAUUGAGAUAUUGGAUCCUUUUAAAUUCUUUGUACUGCUCAUGACCAGUUGCCAUACACCGCAGAAUGUCAAUUGCCUACAAGGUAAAUUUCACAUCGGUCGACUUACCCUCCUGUCACUCCUGAUAAUGCACUCAUGGUUUAUGGGUUGUUUUAGUAGUAUGUGGUGAACUAUAAACUGUUACAAUGGGAGGAGUUUUUUUUUUAAACCUCUUAAAAGUUGAUGUAUAUAUAUCCUUACCACUAAGCAUAUCUUUUCAAUUAGGCAUGUGGCAAUUCCUUUCUUGAUGUUUUUAGGGAAAAUGAGCCAAAUAAUAUUUUAAAAAAUGUAUAAGCCAAGCUGGUUUCUAUCCUUUCUUCUAUUAAACUCAGGAUCACACAAGUAGGCAUGAGUGUGCACAAUAUUUAUGCCUUGCAUUGUUCUGAGAAUUAGUAAAAGAAUAUCUUGAAAGCAUGAUAUAACUUUGUAUUUGUAUCCAAAAAUAUACAAAGUUGUUGAAUUAAAAAAAAAAAAUAAUGCAGCUGGGCGUGGUGGCUCACGCCUGUAAUCCCAGCAUUUUGAGAGGCUGAGGCAUGCUUAUUGCUUGAACCCAGGAGUUUGAGACCAUCGUGGGCAACAUGGCAAAACCCUGUCUCUACAGAAAGUGUAAAAAACAGCCAGGAGGGGUGGUGUACAAGUGUCUUAGCUGAGGCUGAGGUGGGAGGAUUGCUUGAGCCCUGGAGGUCGAGGCUGCAGUGAGCAGUGAUCACGCCACUGCACUCCAGCCUGCGCAACGGAGUGAGACCCUGUCUCAAAAUAAUUAUUAUUUGACAUACCAAAUUUGGGCACAGUGACUAGAAACAAAAUUCCACUGAGUUGAGACAGCUAGGUUACAAAAUUAUUAGAUUACAAAAUAUUAGGUUAGAAGUACUACUGCAGAUGUUUAAACAAGGAAGAAAAAUACACAAGUGGCUAGAGGUGAGGAAAGGCCUGUCUCUAAAAGACAGAAUUUGUACUGGGCCUUUAAAGAUGAACAAUGUUGGCCGGGCGCGGUGGCUCACGCCUGUAAUCCCAGCACUUUGGGAGGCCGAGGUGGGCAGAUCACAAGGUCAGGAGAUCGAGACCGUCCUGGCUAAUACGGUGAAACCCUGUCUCCACUAAAAAAAAUACAAAAAAUUAGCCGGGCGUGGUGGCGGGAGCCUGUAGUUCCCAGCUACUCGGGAGGCUGAGGCAGGAGAAUGGUGUGAACCCGGGAGGUGGAGCUUGCAGUGAGCCGAGAUUGUGCCACUGCGCUCCAGCCUGGGCGAAGAGUGAGACUCCGUCUCAAAAAAAAAAAAAAAAAAAAAAAAAGAUGAACAGUGUUUACAAAGUUGGAGCAGAAGGGAAACUGGUGAGAAUAAAAGCUUAGGGUAUAUAUGGAGAAUGAGGACAGGGAAGACACUGGACUGACUGCUCAGAGCAAGGUAGGCGUGUUGAAGACCUAAGUACUGAUAGGAGCUAGAUUAGCCAGGGUAUUGAGAGCCUGGCAGAGGAGUUGAAAUUUGAUAAGGUAGAGAUAGGAAAUCACUGUAGGUUCUUGAAUGGGGAAAGCUUGAGAAGUUUUUGUUUUUGUUUUGAGUCUUUUAAAGGAAGAGCAAUGUGACAGUGGGAUAAUAUAAAUUUUAGAGAGGGACUGGGAUUCAAGGGAGGCUAGUUAGGAUGCUGUUGCAAUAUUCUAGAUGGGAAUUCACAAUAACCCAAACCACAAUUAUAAAAGUUACAUAGAAUUGGAGGAGAAAGGGAAAAACAGGAAUAUUUCAAAGACAAAAACAGUAAGAUUAGUGACCAAAUGCAAGUAAGAUGGCAGAAAAGAUAAUUCACAGUAUUCCCUGAUUUCUAGCUUGGGGAACUGGAAAAAUUGUGGUAUCACAGACAUAAAUGAGGACAUUAGGGAAAAAAAUCUAUUUGGGAGAACAAGACUAUUCAGUUUGGGAUUGUUGAAGCUAUGAUUUGACAUGUCCUGGCAAAAGUUGGAAAUAAAGAACAGUCAGAUUAGCCUGAUAGUGGUGUGCAGGAAGAAGGACUGCAAAUGGGACAUCCAGGCUAGGAAAUAGAAGGGUUUGGAGGCACAGGUGAUAUUUUUUUCAUGACUUCUUCCAGCUGAAGGUGGUGCCUUUUAGAAAAGAAAGGAGUAAAUAGGAAUAGAACAGUUAGCUCCCCAGAUGGUGUCGAAGAACAAAAUGAGAUUUUAUUUCUGGGCCAUUGUUUAAGAUCCUGGAACCGAUGAGUUUUUGGCAAGAAAUCAGGGAGUCACGAGGAAGAAAAAAAAAGAUUUUUUUUCUUUUUCUUUUUUUUUUUUUGAGAUGGAGUCUUGCUCUGUUGCUGAUGCUGGAGUGCAGUGGCACAAUCUUGGCUCACUGCAACCUCCGUCUCCUGGGUUCAAGCAGUUCUCCUACCUCAGCCUCCUGAGUAGCUGGGAUUACAGGCACCUGCCACCAUUCCCAGCUAAUUUUUGCAUUUUUAGUAGAGACAGGAUUUUACCAUGUUGGCCAGGCAGGUCUCGAACUCCUGACCUCAGGUGAUCUGCCUACCUCGGCCUCCCAAAGUGCUGGGAUUACAGGCAUGAGCCAGCGUGCCUGGUCUCUUUUUUGUUUUUUAAGCGGGAGGAGAGGAUCAUUGGGAGGGAAAUAGGAAAUUGUUGAAAGGAAGGAAAGAAAGAACCAAGUGAAAAAAUAAAGGUCUAAAAGAAAUAAUAAUAUUGUAGAAGAUACCCAGUGUUUCAUAAAGUUGUUAUAGGUGAAAGGAAGCCAAAUUUAUUGCUAACAUUUAUUGAGAGUUUACUAUAUGCCAGCACUGUGGCAAAUUGUUUAUAUGCAUUAUUUUAUUUAAUUCUUACAGUAAGUUCAACUUUUUUUCCCACUUGACAUUAUAUAGUGGACAUCGUUUUUGUUUUGUUUUGUUUUGAGACAGAGUCUCGCUCUGUCACCCAGGCUGGAGUGCAGUAGCACAAUCUUGGCUCACUGCAACCUCUGCUUCCUGAAUUCAAGUGAUUCUCAUGCCUCAGCCUCCCGAGUAGCUGGAAUUACAGACACAUACCACCAGGCCCGGCUAAAUUUAGUAUUUUUAGUAGAAAUGGCAUUUCACCAUGUUGGCCAGGCUGGCCAACUCCUCUCAAACUUCUGGCCUCAAGUGAUCCGCCCGCCUCAGCCUCCCAAAAUGCUGGGAUUACAGGUGUGAGCCACCGUGCCUACACUGUCAUUUUUAAUAGAUAGCAUAGUAUUCCAUUGUAUGAACAUUCAUUGUAGUAAGCUACAAUGAACUCUCCUGUAUGUACAUUUUCCCCACAUUUUUUGGUAUAUUCUUUUUCUUAAGUAACAGAUAAACAUUUUAAUUCUAUUUUUGGAUAAUAUCACAAUUCAAAAAUAAAAAUGUAAAAAAAUAAAUAACAAAAAGGUUUUCUUCCAUUCUUGUUCCUCCUGUCACCUGAACCACCAUUAGUUUUCUUGGCAUCUUUAUAUAAUUUCUUUGUUAUGUAAACAAAUAUAAAUACGUAUUCUUAUUCCCCCCCUUUUUUAUUCAGAAUGUAAAAAGCAUCUUGUGAUCAUCUCUUUAGCAUAAAAUCUUAAAAGUGGUAUUGCUGAGUAGAGGAUAGUUAAAAUCUUAAUACAUAUGGUCCAACUGUUCACGAGAGAGGUUGUACAAUUUAACCUUUCUACCAACAAUGCAUGAGUGUUACUAAAUUCAUGUUAUUUAUGUUCUAAUUUCAGUGUAUUUUUAUAUCUCAAAACUUAUGGGGAGUCCAGAAUAAAUGUUUAAAAAUCACUAUAAUUUAUAAGGUGAAUUCUGGUAUUAUACAGAAUUGAUUAUACAAAAUACUUUGGACUUAACUAAUAAUUUAUAACAGGCAAAUGGACCCAAUGAGAAGGAAAGGUUUGACCUAAGUUAUUAUUUAUCUUUCUGUGUUUUGCUUGUUGGAUAGGUGGAGAAACAGGUAGGAAUGAAAAGAUGGAAAAAUCCGUUUGUGGUAUAAAGAUAGAAGAUAGAGCUGAAUUAAACAAGUAAGCAAAGAGAAAUGGAGACAGACUUCAGAUGAGAGUGAAAAAAGGGUAAACAAUUCCAAAUUGAUUAUCUGAAGAAAUGGAUACUUCUCCCUCCAGAAAAUAUCCAGUUAAAAAACGGGUGAAAAUACAUCCCAACACAGUGAUGGUGAAAUAUACUUCUCAUUAUCCCCAGCCUGGCGAUGAUGGAUAUGAAGAAAUCAAUGAAGGCUAUGGAAAUUUUAUGGAGGAAAAUCCAAAGAAAGGUCUGCUGAGUGAAAUGAAAAAAAAAGGGAGAGCUUUCUUUGGAACCAUGGAUACCCUACCUCCACCAACAGAAGACCCAAUGAUCAAUGAGAUUGGACAAUUCCAGAGCUUUGCAGAAAAAAACAUUUUUCAAUCCCGAAAAAUGUGGAUAGUGCUGUUUGGAUCUGCUUUGGCUCAUGGAUGUGUAGCUCUUAUCACUAGGCUUGUUUCUGAUCGGUCUAAAGUUCCAUCUCUAGAACUGAUUUUUAUCCGUUCUGUUUUUCAGGUCUUAUCUGUGUUAGUUGUGUGUUACUAUCAGGAGGCCCCCUUUGGACCCAGUGGAUACAGAUUACGACUCUUCUUUUAUGGUGUAUGCAAUGUCAUUUCUAUCACUUGUGCUUAUACAUCAUUUUCAAUAGUUCCUCCCAGCAAUGGGACCACUAUGUGGAGAGCCACAACUACAGUCUUCAGUGCCAUUUUGGCUUUUUUACUCGUAGAUGAGAAAAUGGCUUAUGUUGACAUGGCUACAGUUGUUUGCAGCAUCUUAGGUGUUUGUCUUGUCAUGAUCCCAAACAUUGUUGAUGAAGACAAUUCUUUGUUAAAUGCCUGGAAAGAAGCCUUUGGGUACACCAUGACUGUGAUGGCUGGACUGACCACUGCUCUCUCAAUGAUAGUAUACAGAUCCAUCAAGGAGAAGAUCAGCAUGUGGACUGCACUGUUUACUUUUGGUUGGACUGGGACAAUUUGGGGAAUAUCUACUAUGUUUAUUCUUCAAGAACCCAUCAUCCCAUUAGAUGGAGAAACCUGGAGUUAUCUCAUUGCUAUAUGUGUCUGUUCUACUGCAGCAUUCUUAGGAGUUUAUUAUGCCUUGGACAAAUUCCAUCCAGCUUUGGUUAGCACAGUACAACAUUUGGAGAUUGUGGUAGCUAUGGUCUUGCAGCUUCUCGUGCUGCACAUAUUUCCUAGCAUCUAUGAUGUUUUUGGAGGGGUAAUCAUUAUGAUUAGUGUUUUUGUCCUUGCUGGCUAUAAACUUUACUGGAGGAAUUUAAGAAAGCAGGACUACCAGGAAAUACUAGACUCUCCCAUUAAAUGAAUACCUGAUUAUUAUUGUCUCAUUAAUGUUCAGUUAUUAUGUAUACUGCCAUUUUAAUGUUUACCUAUGAAUGUCUUUUGUGUUAUAUAACUGACAGAGUGCUAUAAAAUAUAUAAUAUAUACAAAUGCAGAAAAUUUAUUCUAGUCUAAUAUAUUCAAAUACAAAUAUUAAAUAUAUGAAAUACGUUA